CCAGGCUCCUUCUCUAUAAAGUGGGAUCUAUCAUGACCAGCCUACCUUAUCAAUAUAGGAGAGAAAAUCUUCAUGCCUGAAGAUAUACCCCUGCUCCCUGGCUCCCCACGCCGGCUGAGCCCUCAGGCAGGGUCCAGAGGGGGCCAGGGCCCCAAACAUGGACAGCAGUGUCUCAAGAUGCCAGGUCCCCGGGCCCCAGGUCUGCAGGGCGGUUCCAACAGAGAUCCUGGCCAGCCCUGCGGUGGAGAGAGCACCCGCAGCAGCUCUGUCAUCAACAACUAUCUGGAUGCCAAUGAGCCUGUGUCCUUGGAGGCCCGUCUUAGCCGCAUGCACUUCCAUGACAGUCAGAGGAAGGUCGACUAUGUACUUGCCUACCACUACCGGAAACGCGGGGUGCACCUGGCCCAAGGCUUCCCUGGCCACUCGCUGGCUAUCGUCUCCAAUGGGGAGACAGGCAAGGAGCCUCAUGCUGGGGGCCCAGGUGACAUUGAGCUGGGACCGCUCGAUGCCCUGGAGGAGGAGAGGAAGGAGCAGCGGGAGGAAUUUGAGCACAAUCUGAUGGAGGCUGGACUGGAGCUUGAGAAGGACUUGGAGAAUAAAAGCCAGGGAUCCAUCUUUGUCCGGAUACACGCCCCGUGGCAGGUGCUGGCCAGAGAGGCAGAAUUCUUGAAGAUCAAAGUUCCUACCAAGAAAGAGAUGUACGAGAUCAAAGCAGGAGGCAGCAUUGCAAAGAAGUUCAGCGCGGCUCUGCAGAAGCUGAGCUCGCACCUGCAGCCCCGAGUUCCAGAACACAGCAACAACAAGAUGAAAAACCUCUCCUACCCAUUCUCCAGGGAGAAGAUGUACCUGUACAACAUCCAGGAAAAGGACACCUUCUUUGAUAAUGCCACCCGCAGCCGCAUUGUGCACGAGAUCCUGAAGCGCACAGCCUGCUCCCGAGCCAACAACACGAUGGGUAUUAACUCUCUGAUCGCAAACAAUAUCUAUGAGGCUGCCUACCCUCUUCAUGACGGUGAAUACGAUAGUCCAGAGGACGAUAUGAAUGACAGGAAGCUGCUAUAUCAAGAAUGGGCGCGCUAUGGAGUGUUCUAUAAGUUCCAACCUAUUGACCUCAUCAGAAAGUAUUUUGGAGAAAAAAUUGGACUGUAUUUUGCCUGGCUGGGAUUAUAUACAUCAUUCCUCAUCCCAUCUUCUGUAAUUGGAGUGAUUGUGUUUCUUUAUGGAUGUGCAACAAUUGAAGAAGAUAUUCCCAGCAGAGAGAUGUGUGACCAGCAGAAUGCCUUCACCAUGUGUCCCCUGUGUGACAAGUCCUGUGAUUACUGGAACCUCAGCUCAGCCUGUGGGACCGCGCAGGCCAGCCACCUGUUUGACAACCCUGCCACCGUCUUCUUCUCUAUCUUCAUGGCUCUGUGGGCUACCAUGUUCCUGGAAAACUGGAAGAGGCUACAGAUGCGACUGGGCUACUUUUGGGACCUGACUGGCAUAGAAGAGGAAGAAGAACGUGCCCAGGAACAUUCCAGGCCUGAGUAUGAAACCAAAGUUCGAGAGAAAAUGCUAAAGGAGAGCAACCAGUCUGCUGUCCAGAAAUUGGAAACAAACACGACGGAGUGUGGCGAUGAGGAUGAUGAAGAUAAACUGACCUGGAAGGAUCGUUUCCCAGGUUACCUGAUGAACUUUGCCUCCAUCUUAUUCAUGAUUGCCCUGACAUUCUCAAUCGUCUUUGGGGUGAUAGUGUAUCGAAUAACAACUGCAGCCGCUCUGUCUCUCAAUAAGGCUACACGCUCCAAUGUCCGGGUGACAGUGACAGCAACAGCAGUCAUCAUCAACCUCGUGGUCAUCCUCAUCCUGGACGAGAUCUACGGCGCUGUGGCCAAGUGGCUCACCAAAAUUGAGGUUCCGAAAACAGAACAGACUUUUGAAGAGCGCCUGAUCCUCAAAGCUUUCUUGCUCAAGUUUGUCAAUGCCUACUCCCCCAUCUUCUAUGUGGCCUUUUUCAAAGGGAGGUUUGUGGGCAGGCCUGGAAGCUACGUCUAUGUAUUCGAUGGUUACCGCAUGGAAGAGUGUGCUCCAGGGGGCUGUCUCAUGGAGCUCUGCAUUCAGCUCAGCAUCAUCAUGUUGGGGAAGCAGUUGAUCCAGAACAACAUCUUUGAGAUUGGAGUCCCGAAGCUAAAGAAACUAUUUCGAAAGCUGAAAGAUGAGACCGAAGCUGGAGAAACUGACUCUGCCCAUUCGAAACAUCCAGAGCAGUGGGACCUAGACUACAGCUUGGAACCAUACACAGGACUGACUCCGGAGUACAUGGAAAUGAUCAUCCAGUUUGGUUUUGUCACCCUCUUCGUGGCCUCCUUUCCCCUGGCACCUGUGUUUGCCCUCCUCAACAACGUCAUUGAAGUGCGGCUCGAUGCAAAGAAGUUUGUUACAGAGCUGAGACGGCCGGAUGCUGUAAGAACCAAAGAUAUCGGAAUCUGGUUUGACAUUCUCUCUGGAAUUGGCAAGUUCUCUGUUAUCAGCAACGCUUUUGUCAUUGCGAUCACCUCCGACUUUAUCCCCCGCCUGGUGUACCAGUACUCCUACAGUCACAAUGGGACUCUGCACGGCUUUGUCAACCACACCCUCUCCUUUUUCAACGUCAGCCAGCUGAAGGAGGGGACGCAGCCAGAAAACUCACAGUUUGACCAGGAGGUUCAGUUCUGCAGGUUUAAGGAUUACCGAGAGCCGCCAUGGGCCCCGAACCCUUAUGAGUUUUCGAAACAGUACUGGUUUAUUCUGUCCGCCCGUCUGGCUUUUGUCAUAAUCUUCCAGAACCUCGUGAUGUUCCUGAGCGUCCUCGUGGACUGGAUGAUUCCAGACAUCCCCACGGACAUCAGCGACCAGAUCAAGAAAGAGAAGAGCUUAUUAGUGGAUUUCUUCCUGAAAGAGGAGCAUGAGAAGCUCAAGCUGAUGGAUGAGCCGGCUCUGAGGAGCCCAGGAGGUGGGGAUCGAAGCAGGAGCCGGGCAGCCAGCUCAGCACCUUCAGGCCAAAGCCAGCUGGGCAGCAUGAUGUCGUCAGGCUCUCAGCACACCAAUGUGUGAGCAGUUCAGCCUGCAGCAGAGGAGGGCACGGCAGCAGAGACACGCACAUGCACGUAAGCAUGUUCCUACACCCACAUGGCGUGCUGUCUGUCUGCAGGGGCCUGGCUUGAUGGGGUCUUGAAGAGGGGGCAGUGUGUAAAAAGAAAGAGCCUGACAGAAUGAGUGUAGGAAGGAAGAGAAAUGAUGCUACAUCUCAGAAACUUCAAGCUUAAGUUUCUUUUAGGUCCCCUUUUAAGCUGCAUCCUUUUGAGGGAUUGGAACCCCACUGGGGUCUCUCCACCCCAGAGUCUCAGGCACCGCGAGCAUUCCCAUGUACCCUGGGGCACCCUCUUGUACUUCACCAUCAUUUCUGACUUUGACCAGCUGUAAGAGAAAUGCAGUCAGGAGCACAGCAUCCCCUACUUACUAUCACUACAAGAAAACUGAGUCACUUGCAGUGGGGCUGCCACAGUCUCAGCAGAUGCAAAUUAAGUUACAAGGCUGAAUGGUGCAGCCGCUGGACCUGAUAGUAAGGUGCAAAGGUCCAAACCUGGGCUUGUCUCCACUUCACGUCACAAAAACGUUUGGAGCUAAAUGCAGAUAACCAUCAUUUUAUGAAAGUUCAGAUUUAAAAUAAUAAAAUAAAUGGACACAUUCUUUAUAAA